GCGGUGGGUGGAGGGUGAAGGAUGUCUGUCUUUGUUUAAAUGCUUGACAUUCCUGUCGUCGUGCUUGCUUGCGGGGGUAGACCGUGUGUGCGCGCCUGGGGAAUAAACACAUGUUGGAAACCUCGAUAUUAUUUUCUGAGCAGAAACCUGCAGCCUUUAGUAACUGGCAAAGUGUAGCGUCACCUAUCUGGAUAAAAGGGAAAUAAACUUUAAUGGCAACUUUGUGUACCAAAGUGUCCCCAGCUUUCCCAUCUCUCCUUUUGACUUUGUGUCCCUUGACUGUCCCUAUUUCCUGAAGCAAGGCUUCUCCAAUUUUCAUUCACGACCACCGCAGCCGGCCUCAUCAGAUCUCAGGUCUGGUUGUGUUUUUGAACUGAGCCAUUUACUCAUUUAUUUCAGUGGCUGUAAACGAAGAGGCCCGGCUAGGAUUAAGACGACUGAGACGGACUGUAGGUAUUUGGGGAGAAUUUUUACCAUCUCGAAAGAGAGAAAGGGCCGCUGCUGGGAUUUGCUUAGUCUUCAGCUCGCCUGACGUAUCCAUACACAUUUAAGGGCCUCCCCUCAAAGAAAAAUUUAAAGCCGAAAAAAUAAAAUCUGUCCAGUGUGGGUAUUCUUUACGAGACCUGGGUGACGAGGCAGAAUGAUUUAAACAAGACAAACACCAAUAAAGUCAACGAGCAGAUGUAGCGCGCGGUUGUUUGGGCGGGCGCAGGAACAGGAAUGAGGAGGGAGAGGCGGCAGAGAUUUCCAAGCUCUCCCUACAGGGGAUCGUAGAUGCCCGUUGGAUGGAAGUGUGUCUAAGUGUGUGUCAGGGAGCUGGCGAGUAUUUUCCAGUCUGUGAAAGUAGCAUCACCCCAGGGGUGGUGGCUCCUCCUCCGAGGCCAGGGCAGGGAACCCGGCCUUCCCGCUAACCCUCCCGCUGCUGGCACCCGAACCUCUCAGCUCUGUAUCUGCAGCAUCAGCGAGAAAAGCCCCGCGCGCAGGCUCAGUGCGCACCGCCGCAGUCUCGAGCCGGGGGCGGGGGUGGGCUCCGCAGCGCCUUCGCGGCCGGCUAAGUGGCAGUAAAGCCAAAUCCCUCUUACAUUUGGCAAGAACCCGGGUUUAUCGGAACGCCUGCCUCUCUCCAAACCUCCGACCCUGGUUCCCCUUUUUCCCAGGUUGGAGGCAAAUGGGAGAAGCCGUCUCCACUCCGCGGCCUUGCGCCGUGCAUUCCGAUGCGCGGCAAUAUGGUGCAGUGCACUCACUCCCCUCAUCGCCUUACUAAGAUUUUGCAAACUUCAGGCAGCCGCUUGGGCAGAAACGUUGUGCACUCCCUCUUCCCUCUCCAGACCAUAAACUUGAAUAAGCCUCUCCGCAUCUUCAAAGCAUUUGCUCGCGGCUCUGGCGCGCACUCUCCAGGCGCACACUUGAGCGGGGCGCGAAGGAGUGGGCGGCUUUUCCUCAGCGCGCUGCACAUUUCUUCCCGGAUGACUAGGGAGUUGCAGCGCGUCCUUCACAGUGGAGUGGUUUCCUCUUUGCGAGCGGGAGGAAGUCUCCAGCCCGCCCUCCUCACUCUCAUUCCUACCAACUUCGCGGCGGAGCCAAGCCAGCGUGGGAAAUGGGUCCGACGUGUGCUGCAUGGAGAACAGCGAGGACAGACUGCGGGGGCCAAGAAGCCUGCUGGCUUUGCUCCCACCCCCAUCAGUCCCAGGCUCCGACCUUUCUGCCAGAGCAGCAAAGAAGUGGCGGCGGCUUUGCCCUGCAGCGCCGUUCUGGGCAAGCAAAGGAAAUGGGCGGGGUAGGGGUACGGGGGAGGUGAGAGGAGCCCUCGGGGCGCCCUUGCGGCGGCUGGAGCUCCCAGUCCUCUUCCGCCCCCUCUCUAGGGGCUGACACUCUCUCCUCUCGCCGGCGCAGAGGAUGAAUGAAGAGAGAAGCAGUUUCUCCCACCCCCGCCCCAUUUCCGCAGUCUUAGAGCCAGUGUCACAAGUGCUCAGCAAUUUCAUUAAAUGGAACCGGGAGACUUAAUCCCCCCCGGUACCAGACCUCACCGAGGGAAUGUGAUAUCCGGCUUCGCUCCCACCCACCAACCCCCCCCCCCCCCCCCCCCCGGCUUCUCAGACCCGAGGCUGCAUUUAUCUACUCAACCUGAGAGGAAAGGGUUCAGAAGGAAAUGGGAUCGAAAGUGUAACCGCCUGCAAUAAAUUAAAGAGCCUGCUGCUGCUGCUGCUGCUGCUGCUGCUGCUGCUGCUUUGGCGGCCAGAACUGGAGAGAGAAAAUGAGAUCAGUGCCCUAAAGCUUGCAUCGAUCAGAGUGAUUAGACGUCAUCGCAUGUAGGAAGCAAAAUGUUUGAGGGAAUGUUGAAAUGGAGAUUUCUGUUUUUUCUUUAGUGGCUUUUUAAAAAAGAACAAUAAAAGGAAAUACCCCUUUGAAAUCAAGAUGUAAAAAAUGAAAUUGAUUAAAAUAUAAAUAUCAUCCCGUGCUAAUAUGCAUUUAAUAAAACCUUGACAAACGA